ACAAUUCAGUGGUUUUUAGCAUAUGCACAGGAUUGUAUAAUUAUCACCAUUAUCUAAUUUUAGAACAUUUCAUCACCACAAACACUCUGUACACAUUAGCAGUCACUCCUCAUUUCCCUGGUAUCCUCUAAUCAACUUUUUGUGGCUUGUCUAUGGAUUUGUUUAUUCUGGACAUAUGUAAAAAUGAAAUCAUACUAUAUAUGUUAUUGUGUGUCUUGCUGCUUUUACUCAGCAUAAUCAAAGUUCACUCAUAUUGUAGCAUGUAUGGGUAUAUCAUUCUUUCAGAUGACUGUGUGGAUAUAUCACGUUGUAUUUAUCCAUUCAUCAACUGAUGAACAUUUGAUUGUUUCCACUUUUAGGCUAUUAUGAUUAAUGCUGGUAUGAAUAUUUUUGUAGAAGUUUUUGUUGGGCCAUAUGUUUCAGUUCUCUUGGGUAUAUAUCUAGGAGUGGAAUUGCAGCAUAAUAUGUUAGCUGUUGAUGUUUAACCUUUGGAAGAACUACCAGCCUCUUUCCCAAAGCAACUGUACCAUUUCACAUUUCCACCUGAAAUGUAUGAGGGUUUCAGUUCUCUACAUCCUUGUCAGCAUAUGGUAUUGUCUAUCUUUCUGAUUUUAGUCAUCCUUGUGGGUGUGAAGUGGUAGCUCACUGUGGUUUUGAUUUGCAGUUCCCUAAUAACUUAUGAUGUUGAGCAUUUUUUCAUGUGCUUAGUGACCAUUGCAUAUAUUCUUUGGAGAAAUACCUAUUCAAAUUCUUUGCUCAUUUUAAAAUUGGGUUGUAUUUUUAUUGUUGUAAGAGUUCUUUUUAUAUUCUUAACAUUGUGCUCUUAUGUGAUGUAUAAUUUGCAAAUAUUUCUUGUUUUUUUUGAGUUGCCUUUUCACUUUCUUUUUCUCCUUUCCUUUUUUUUUUUUUUUUUUUGAGACGAAGUCUUGCUCUGUCACUCAAGCUGGAAUGCAGUGGUGUGAUCUUGGUUCGCUGCAGCCUCUGCCUCCCCAGCUCAAGCAAUUCUCUUGCCUCAGCCUCCCGAGUAGCUGAUAUUACAAGUGUGCACCAUCAUGCCGGCUAAUUUUUGUAUUUUUAGUAGAGAUGGGGUUUCACCAUGUUGGCCAGGCUGGUCUCGAACUCCUGACCUCAGGUGAUCCACCUGCUUCGGCCUCCCAAAAUGCUGGGAUAACAGGCGUGAGCCACCGUGCCCAGCCUGCCUUUUCAAUUUCUUGAUGAUUCACUUCUUUGAUUUUGUGAUUCACUUUGAAUCACAAAAGUUUUUAAUUUUGAUGAAGUCCAAUCCAUCUCUUUUUUUUCUUUUGUUGCUUGUGCUAAGAAACCACUGCUUGAUCCAAGGUUGCAAAGAUUUACUCCUUUGUUUUCUUCUUAGAGUUUUGUGGUUUAAGCUCUUAUAUUUAGAUCUGGAAGUGCUUUUUUUUUUCUUUUUUUUUUUUGAGACAGAAUCUCACUCUGUCACCCAGGCUGGAGAGCAAUGGUGUGAUCUCGGCUCACGGAAACCUCCACCUCCUGGGUUCAUGCGAUUCUCCUGCCUCAGCCUUUGGAGAAGCUGGGAUUACAAGUGUGUGCCACCACGCUCAGCUAACUUUUGUAUUUUUAGUAGAGAUGGAGUUUCAUCAUGUUGGCCAGGCUGGUCUCGAACUCCUGACCUCUAGUGAUCUGCCUGCCUUGGCUUCCCAAAGUGCUGAAAUUACAGGUGUGAGCCACAGCACCCAGCUCAGAUAUUCUUAGUGUUUUCAAAUUUAACUUUGUUGUGCUUUUACUUGAUGUGGAAAUUUGCAACACUUGAAGUAAAGCUAUUACACUCCGAAAAGUUGUGCAGCAAAUUUAAUGAUGGUCCUUGCCCUAUAUUUGUCUGCUGUUCCUGCCCCUACCCAAAGUUAGUACUCUGCAUUGUGCUGCCUCCUCCCAUGUCAUCUCUCAGGCUAUGGAUGCAAAGUGUCAUUUUAUUUUAUCCUUUUAAAAACAUCAGUUACCCUGACCAGAAGGAAAGAAUUUAGUAUGUUGGUAUAAUGGUGGGACUGUAGGCCGCAGACUGUAGGAAUAGUGUGCUGCAGGUGAGCAAGUGAAACUUCAUUCUUAGAUUAAUAAUUUAUGAUAGCUAUUAGUGGGAGAUAGAUUGCUUAUAUGGAACAGACUCAAGAUUAUUGUUUAGUCUAUGCAGAGGAAGCAAAAUGUAUAAAAUUGUGGAGGAAAGAACAACAGCAAGUCAUUCAGGAUGUCUAGAGCAAAUACUCAGGAUGGAGGUUGGAGAUGCGUUUGAGAGAGAGGGAGAGCAUGAUAAUGUGUGCCAGGCUAUAGAAUUUGGUGUUUAACCUGAUGGAGAAAGGGAGUAAUAGAUUCCAAGUGGAAUAAAUUAUUUUAGUUCCCAAAAUGGAAAUAGUGAUUUUUUUUUCUGAUUGUAAAGGGAAUACAUGUUUGUCAUAACAUGCAAACAAGUAAUAAAAAAAUAGGCAGUGAAAAGUCCCUGUAAUCCCAUUCACUAGAGAUAACCACUGCUUAACAGUUUGCUGUAUAGUUUUACAGAGGAGAAUUUUGUGAUCAGUUUUGCAGCAGUGUGGUUGGUGGAAAGGACAAAAGUUGGAUGACAUUGGAAGUAGAUGGCUGUUAGGUCCAAAUAGGAAUGACGAGGACCUGUUUCUUAGUGGUAGCUGUGGGGGUAGAAAAGGUGCAGAACUGGGGAAAAGUUCAAGGGAUUUAUUUAGGAGCUAGGAUUCAGUGAUCAGUUUGGCAACUGAGUGAAGGACUGAUAAGUGGCCAGGAUGAGAGUUGAUUGGAUUUCCCAGAACCUGGGACCAAACUGUGACAUCAUUUGAGCAGGCAUAAAAGGGACAAAUAGCAGUUGUUGCUAGCAGCAUAAUUUCAGAGUGGAAAGUCUGUCCUUUUGUUCUUAUUUUCCUCCUGUGUUUCUGGGUUUAUUUAGAAGGGGAGGGUACAAGUAAGAAUUCAAUUUUGUUUGGACAGAUAAAAGCUAUUAUAUCAUGCCCUUAUCUCUAAUUGUUUCUUUUAUUAGUUGAGUAUAGCAGAUUUCUUUGAGAAGUUGCUUCUGUUUUGGUGUGUAAUUAUAGCAUGAGCUUUUAAACUUCACAAAGUUUAUCUUGGAAUCUUUACAAUUUUAUUCUGGGGAAUUGGGAUUGCGGUGAGGGAGCCACUUUGGCAAGUUAUUGACAGAGAUUCUUUGACUCUAAAGUAAGAGCUGAUUGUAUCUCUGAAUAGGUUUUUUUUUUUUUUUUCAUUUGAGACAGGGUCUCACGUUGUCACCUAGGCAGUGACAUGAUCUUGGCUCACCGCAGCUUCCACCUCCUGAGCUCAAGCAAUCCUCCCACCUCAGCCUCCUGAGUAGGUGGGACUACCAGGAUGUGGCAACACGCCUGGCUAAUUUUUGUAUUUUUUUGUAGAGAUGGGGUUUCACAAUGUUGCCCAGACUCGUCUUGAACUCCUGAGCUCAUGCCAUCUGCCUGUGUUGGCCUCCCAAAGUGCUAGGAUUAGAGGUGUGAGCCACUGCACCCAGCCCGAAUCGGGUCUUGCUUUCACCAAGUUCUGCUAUGUUUCUUAUUCCUGGGAACAGGCAACUGUCUGAUAUAGUUUGGAUAUUUGUCCCCUCCAAAUCUCAGGUUGGAAAUUGAUCUCCGGUGUUGGAAGUGGGGCUAACUGGGAAGUGUUUGGGUCAUGGGGGCAGAUCCCUUAUGACUGGCUUGGUGCUGUCCUAGGUAAUGAGUGAAUUCUUGCUCUAUCGGUUCCCAGGGAGAUCUGGUUGUUCAAAAAGAAUCUGGGAUAUCCCUCCUCUCUUUCUUGCUCCUUCUGUUGCCAUGUGACACACUGGCUCCCCUUCCCCUUGUGCCGUGAUUGAAAGCUUCCUGAGGCCCUCAUCGGAAGCAGAUGCUGGUGCCAUGUUUCUUAUAUGGCCUGCAGAACCAUGAGCCAAAUAAAAUUCUUUUCUUUAUAAAUUAGCCAGUUUGAGGUAUUCCUUUAUAGCAACGCAAAAUGGACUAAUACACUAAUAUCUCACACAUUUUCUGUCCUUACAACUUUUUGGAUGGUUAAUCAAGAUAAUGUGCAUAAAGAACUACAUAAUGCUAUGUAGUAGGCACUAAAAGACACUGGCUUCUUCUAUCUUACCUAAGAACAAACUUGAGAUUAUAAAAAAAUGAAAAGUUAAAAUCUCUUUCUUGCAAGUUUCAUUUUUCCUUUAAAAAAUUUUAAAAGUAUAUCUAAAUGCCACCUCCUGUCUGCUUUCUCAUCUCUGGAAGAUGGGAAAUCUUCCAGAGAUGAGAAAUGUCCAUGAUACUCCUCCUUUGCACUCAUAGUACCUUGGAACAUUCUUCUUUCAAGCAGCUCAUCAUUCAGUAUUUUAAUUGUGCAGUACAAUGCCUGGCACAUAAUUGAUCCUCAAUAAAUAUUUGUUGUAGAGAUGUCUUGAAAUGAGAUAAAAUGUUCUCCAUUGCCUUCUCUUGAACAGCUGAACAACCGUACUGAAAAAAAUAGGUUUGUUUAUCCACUCAGAAGCUUGGUUUGUUUUGGAAGAAAAAUGGUAUUUUGUUAGGAAGUUUAAGUAUUACCGUCUUAAAAUAAAUUUAAAUAAAAAAAAAUAAAUUCUGAUGUCUUCUGAUAUAUACCUUGAUAGAAGAUUUUGUGUUGUGAUUUGAAAUGAAGGCAACAGUGUGACUUUUUUUUUUUUUUUUUUUGAGACAGAGUGUCACUCUGUCAUCAGGCUGGAGUGCAGUGGUGCGAUCUUGGCUCACUGCAACCUCUGCCUCCCAGGUUCAAGUGAUUCUUCUGCCUCAGUCUCCCGAGCAGCUAGGAUUACAGGUGCAUGCCACCACGCCCGGCUAAUUUUUGUAUUUUUUUUUUUUUUUGAGAUGGAGUCUCACUCCGUCGCCCAGGCUGGAGUGCAGUGGCGCCAUCUCUGUUCACUGCAACCUCCAUCUCCUGGGUUCAAGUGAUUCUCCAGUCUCAGCUUCCCGAGUAGCUGGGAUUACAGACAUGUGCCACCACACCCAGCUAAUUUUUAUAUUUUUAGUAGAGACGGGGUUUUGCCAUGUUGGCCAGGAUGGUCUCAAUCUCUUGACCUUGUGAUCUGCCUGCCUCGGCCUCCUGAAGUGCUGGGAUUACAGGUGUGAGCCAUUGCGCCUGGCCUAACUUUUGUAUUUUUGUAGAGACAGGGUUUCACCAUGUUGGCCAGGCUGGUCUCAAACUCCUGACCUCAAGUAAUCUGCCCACCUCAGCCUCUCAAAGUGCUGGGAUUACAGGUGUGAGCCACAGCGCCCAGCCUCCUUUAAGUGCUUGAGAAUAUGAGAUUUUAAAAAAUUUAUUUAUUUAUUGUAGAGAUGGGGUCUUACUGUUUUGCCCAGGCUGGCCUCAAACUCCUGAGUUCAAGUGAUCCUCUUGCCUCAGCCUUCCAAAGUGCUGGGAUUACAGGCGUGAGGCACCGUGCCCAGCCAAGGUCUUUGAAGUACUUAAGAAUGACUGUUUCUCUGAACUUCAUUUAUUCAUCUAACAUUUAUUGAGUUCUUCUUUAUGCCCUAGUCUAGACCUUGUGCUAAGGGCUAUGGAAAGUCAAAGAGUUACAAAUCGUUUCCUAUCCUCAAGACCUUUCACUUUGAUGACAGAGGAAGACCAAAACAUCUCCACAUUACAUUAUAGUUUCAUAGGUAAGGUAAGCACAAAGGAACAUUGUCCAUUCAUAUUUGGUACACGAGUUUGUUGUUUAUGCCUGUGUAUAGGGUGAGUGCAGCAGGAAAGCUUUUUGGAGGAGCUGAGACUUGAAGGAUACAUGGAGAAAGACUGGGGAAAGGCAUUUAUUCCCAGCAAAGUGUAUAUACCUGUGCAAAGGCAGGGUGGUAUUAGAAGUCUAUAAUUGGUUCUUUAUGGCUGGAGGUAAGGCUGCAGAUACAAGCAGAGGUCAAAGGAAUCAUGAAAGAUAAGGAAUCAUGUGCCAAGAUAAGGAAUUUAACGAUUCUGAUUUGUAUUUUAGAAAGAUCACUGAUACAGCAGUGUAAAGGUGGGUAUAUUAGAUUUAGGUUCACCUACAGUACAAAACAGGUGGUCUCAACAAAAUAGAGGUAUAUUUCUCACACUGAAGUCCAGUUUUGGCAUGAUGACUGUAGGAUCAUCAAAGACCUGAGUUCCUUCUGUCUGCUUGACUGUCCCUUGGCACAGCUUCCAUUACCCUUAUUGUCCAGAAUGACUGCUGGAGUGCCAUCCACCAUAUUUGAACUACAGACACACUUCUAGCUAAGUUCCCUUUAAGUAGCUAUCUUGGAAGUGUCUCAUCCAGUGACUUCCACUUCUAGCUAAUUGACCAGUCGUAGCAGCGAGGAAGGCUGGGAAAUGUACACUUCACCUGGAUACAUGCCACCCAGAAUAAAACCAUGGUCUGUUCCUAAGGAAGAAAGGGAGAAUGGGUGUAUGCUAGGCAGCCAGUAGUGUUGCCACAAAGAGGAUGGAUAAUGGAGUUAGGGAGAACAAUUUAGUACAAUUUACCCAAGUAGUAAUACGUGUGAUUGCUUACACAAGACUGGUUUGGUUAAUAAUGCAAGAAUUGAAACUCUGUACUAACUCUGAGUAAAAGCCAUUCUGCUGGGAAACCUAGAGGACUCCAGUGGUUAUUUUGAUGACAUAACUGUUUUAGUGGGGCAAAAAUUGUACUUUAAUUAUUUUAACCUUUGAAUUAAAAGACUUCCAAUUAAACUUUUAGUAAAAUUAAAUCAGUACUAAAGAGAAUUAAUGUUUUUAAGAAAGACAUUGAUAGGAAUUCCUUUUUUAAAAAAGUGUGUAGUAUGAUUUUUAAAAACUAUAUGACAAUAUACAUUAAACGGGUUUACAGUGGUUUUUUGGGAGAUGAAAUAAUUUUAUUUUUCUUUUUUGCAAUUCCUUUUUUAGAUUUUCUAUACUUAGCACAUGUUACUUUUUUAAAAAUUGUGAUAAACAUAACAAGAAAUUUACCAUCUUAACUAUUUUUAGGUAUACAGUUCAGUGGGAUUGAGUACAUUCAUAUUGUUGUGCUACCAUCACCACCAUCCAUCCACAGACCUCUUUCAUCUUACAAAUCUGAAACUCUGGACCUAUUAAAGAAUAAGUGCCCAUUCUCCCCUUCCCCCAGCACAUGGCAACCACAUUCUGCUUUCUGUCUCUAUGAAUUUGACUACUGUACCUACCUGAUGUACAUGGGAUCUAUAGUGUUUGUCCUUUUGUGAGGGCUUAUAUGACAUAGCAUAAUGCCUUCAAGCUUGUUGUAGCAUGUGUCAGAAUUUCCCUCCUUUUUAUGGCUAAUAUUCUGUUACAUGUAUAUGCUACCAAUUGUUUGUCCACUCAUCCGUUAAGGGAAGCUUGGAUUGCUCCCACAUUUUGACUACUGUGAAUAAUGGUGCUACAAACAUGGGUAUAGAAGUAUCUCCUUGAGUCCCUGCUUUUCGUUCUUUUGACUCCAUACCCAGAAGUGGAACUGCUGGAUCAUAUGAUUCCAGGAGGGCUUCGUGUAUGGACCUCAAGCGUUGGAGGUAGCAGACUUUUCAGCAGAAGAAAAGAUGAAAAGGAAUAUGCAUUGAAGCAAAUUGAAGGCACAGGAAUAUCCAUGUCGGCUUGUAGAGAGAUUGCACUUUUGCGAGAAUUGAAGCACCCUAAUGUGAUUGCAUUGCAGAAGGUGUUCCUUUCUCACAGUGACAGGAAGGUAUGGCUGCUGUUUGAUUAUGCAGAGCAUGACUUGUGGCAUAUUAUUAAGUUUCACCGUGCAUCAAAAGCAAAUAAAAAGCCCAUGCAGUUGCCAAGAUCUAUGGUUAAAUCCUUACUUUACCAGAUUCUUGAUGGUAUCCAUUACCUCCAUGCAAAUUGGGUGCUUCACAGAGACUUGAAACCAGCAAAUAUCCUAGUAAUGGGAGAAGGUCCUGAGAGGGGGAGAGUCAAAAUAGCUGACAUGGGUUUUGCCAGAUUAUUCAAUUCUCCUCUAAAGCCACUAGCAGAUUUGGAUCCAGUAGUUGUGACAUUUUGGUAUCGGGCUCCAGAACUUUUGCUUGGUGCAAGGCAUUAUACAAAGGCCAUUGAUAUAUGGGCAAUAGGUUGUAUAUUUGCUGAAUUGUUGACUUCGGAACCUAUUUUUCACUGUCGUCAGGAAGAUAUAAAAACAAGCAAUCCCUUUCAUCAUGAUCAACUGGAUCGGAUAUUUAGUGUCAUGGGGUUUCCUGCAGAUAAAGACUGGGAAGAUAUUAGAAAGAUGCCAGAAUAUCCCACACUUCAAAAAGACUUUAGAAGAACAACGUAUGCCAACAGUAGCCUCAUAAAGUACAUGGAGAAACACAAGGUCAAGCCUGACAGCAAAGUGUUCCUCUUGCUUCAGAAACUCCUGACCAUGGAUCCAACCAAGAGAAUUACCUCGGAGCAAGCUCUGCAGGAUCCCUAUUUUCAGGAGGACCCUUUGCCAACAUUAGAUGUAUUUGCCGGCUGCCAGAUUCCAUACCCCAAACGAGAAUUCCUUAAUGAAGAUGAUCCUGAAGAAAAAGGUGACAAGAAUCAGCAACAGCAGCAGAACCAGCAUCAGCAGCCCACAGCCCCUCCACAGCAGGCAGCAGCCCCUCCACAGGCGCCCCCACCACAGCAGAACAGCACCCAGACCAACGGGACCGCAGGUGGGGCUGGGGCCGGGGUCGGGGGCACCGGAGCAGGGUUGCAGCACAGCCAGGACUCCAGCCUGAACCAGGUGCCUCCAAACAAGAAGCCACGGCUAGGGCCUUCAGGCGCAAACUCAGGUGGACCUGUGAUGCCCUCGGAUUAUCAGCACUCCAGUUCUCGCCUGAAUUACCAAAGCAGCGUUCAGGGAUCCUCUCAGUCCCAGAGCACACUUGGCUACUCUUCCUCGUCUCAGCAGAGCUCACAGUACCACCCAUCUCACCAGGCCCACCGGUACUGACCAGCUCCCGUUGGGCCAGGCCAGCCCAGCCCAGAGCACAGGCUCCAGCAAUAUGUCUGCAUUGAAAAGAACCAAAAAAAUGCAAACUAUGAUGCCAUUUAAAACUCAUACACAUGGGAGGAAAACCUUAUAUACUGAGCAUUGUGCAGGACUGAUAGCUCUUCUUUAUUGACUUAAAGAAGAUUCUUGUGAAGUUUCCCCAGCACCCCUUCCCUGCAUGUGUUCCAUUGUGACUUCUCUGAUAAAGCGUCUGAUCUAAUCCCAGCACUUCUGUAACCUUCAGCAUUUCUUUGAAGGAUUUCCUGGUGCACCUUUCUCAUGCUGUAGCAAUCACUAUGGUUUAUCUUUUCAAAGCUCUUUUAAUAGGAUUUUAAUGUUUUAGAAACAGGAUUCCAGUGGUGUAUAGUUUUAUACUUCAUGAACUGAUUUAGCAACACAGGUAAAAAUGCACCUUUUAAAGCACUACGUUUUCACAGACAAUAACUGUUCUGCUCAUGGAAGUCUUAAACAGAAACUGUUACUGUCCCAAAGUACUUUACUAUUACGUUCGUAUUUAUCUAGUUUCAGGGAAGGUCUAAUAAAAAGACAAGCGGUGGGACAGAGGGAACCUACAACCAAAAACUGCCUAGAUCUUUGCAGUUAUGUGCUUUAUGCCACGAAGAACUGAAGUAUGUGGUAAUUUUUAUAGAAUCAUUCAUAUGGAACUGAGUUCCCAGCAUCAUCUUAUUCUGAAUAGCAUUCAGUAAUUAAGAAUUACAAUUUUAACCUUCAUGUAGCUAAGUCUACCUUAAAAAGGGUUUCAAGAGCUUUGUACAGUCUCGAUGGCCCACACCAAAACGCUGAAGAGAGUAACAACUGCACUAGGAUUUCUGUAAGGAGUAAUUUUGAUCAAAAGACGUGUUACUUCCCUUUGAAGGAAAAGUUUUUAGUGUGUAUUGUACAUAAAGUCGGCUUCUCUAAAGAACCAUUGGUUUCUUCACAUCUGGGUCUGCGUGAGUAACUUUCUUGCAUAAUCAAGGUUACUCAAGUAGAAGCCUGAAAAUUAAUCUGCUUUUAAAAUAAAGAGCAGUGUUCUCCAUUCGUAUUUGUAUUAGAUAUAGAGUGACUAUUUUUAAAGCAUGUUAAAAAUUUAGGUUUUAUUCAUGUUUAAAGUAUGUAUUAUGUAUGCAUAAUUUUGCUGUUGUUACUGAAACUUAAUUCUAUCAAGAAUCUUUUUCAUUGCACUGAAUGAUUUCUUUUGCCCCUAGGAGAAAACUUAAUAAUUGUGCCUAAAAACUAUGGGCGGAUAGUAUAAGACUAUACUAGACAAAGUGAAUAUUUGCAUUUCCAUUAUCUAUGAAUUAGUGGCUGAGUUCUUUCUUAGCUGCUUUAAGGAGCCCCUCACUCCCCAGAGUCAAAAGGAAAUGUAAAAACUUAGAGCUCCCAUUGUAAUGUAAGGGGCAAGAAAUUUGUGUUCUUCUGAAUGCUACUAGCAGCACCAGCCUUGUUUUAAAUGUUUUCUUGAGCUAGAAGAAAUAGCUGAUUAUUGUAUAUGCAAAUUACAUGCAUUUUUAAAAACUAUUCUUUCUGAACUUAUCUACCUGGUUAUGAUACUGUGGGUCCAUACACAAGUAAAAUAAGAUUAGACAGAAGCCAGUAUACAUUUUGCACUAUUGAUGUGAUACUGUAGCCAGCCAGGACCUUACUGAUCUCAGCAUAAUAAUGCUCACUAAUAAUGAAGUCUGCAUAGUGACACUCAUCAAGACUGAAGAUGAAGCAGGUUACGUGCUCCAUUGGAAGGAGUUUCUGAUAGUCUCCUGCUGUUUUACCCCUUCCAUUUUUUAAAAUAAGAAAUUAGCAGCCCUCUGCAUAAUGUAGCUGCCUAUAUGCAGUUUUAUCCUGUGCCCUAAAGCCUCACUGUCCAGAGCUGUUGGUCAUCAGAUGCUUAUUGCACCCUCACCAUGUGCCUGGUGCCCUGCUGGGUAGAGAACACAGAGGACAGGGCAUACUUCUUGUCCUUAAGGAGCUUGUGAUCUGUGACAGUAAGCCCUCCUGGGAUGUCUGUGCCAUGUGAUUGACUUACAAGUGAAACUGUCUUAUAAUAUGAAGGUCUUUUUGUUUACUUCUAAACCCACUUGGGUAGUUACUAUCCCCAAAUCUGUUCUGUAAAUAAUAUUAUGGAAGGGUUUCUAUGUCAGUCUACCUUAGAGAAAGCCAGUGAUUCAAUAUCACAAAAGGCAUUGACGUAUCUUUGAAAUGUUCACAGCAGCCUUUUAACAACAACUGGGUGGUCCUUGUAGGCAGAACAUACUCUCCUAAGUGGUUGUAGGAAAUUGCAAGGAAAAUAGAAGGUCUGUUCUUGCUCUCAAGGAGGUUACCUUUAAUAAAAGAAGACAAACCCAGAUAGAUAUGUAAACCAAAAUACUAUGCCCCUUAAUACUUUAUAAGCAGCAUUGUUAAAUAGUUCUUACGCUUAUACAUUCACAGAACUACCCUGUUUUCCUUGUAUAUAAUGACUUUUGCUGGCAGAACUGAAAUAUAAACUGUAAGGGGAUUUCGUCAGUUGCUCCCAGUAUACAAUAUCCUCCAGGACAUAGCCAGAAAUCUCCAUUCCACACAUGACUGAGUUCCUAUCCCUGCACUGGUACUGGCUCUUUUCUCCUCUUUCCUUGCCUCAGGGUUCGUGCUACCCACUGAUUCCCUUUACCCUUAGUAAUAAUUUUGGAUCAUUUUCUUUCCUUUAAAGGGGAACAAAGCCUUUUUUUUUUUUGAGACGGAGUGUUGCUCUGUCACCCAAGCUGGAGUGCAGUGGCACGAUCUUGGCUCACUCCAACCUCCACCUUCCAGGUUCAAGUGAUUCUCCUGCCUCAGCCUCCCGAGUAGCUGGGACUACGGGCACGCACCACCACGUCUGGCUAAUUUUUGUAUUUUUAGUAGAGAUGGGGUUUCACCCUAUUGGUCAGGCUGGUCUUGAAUUCCUCACCUCAGGUCAUCCGCCUGUCUCGGCCUCCCGAAGUGCUGGGAUUAUAGGUGUGAGCCACCGCACCCAGUUGGGAACAAAGCCUUUUUAACACACGUAAGGGCCCUCAAACCGUGGGACCUCUAAGGAGACCUUUGAAGCUUUUUGAGGGCAAACUUUACCUUUGUGGUCCCCAAAUGAUGGCAUUUCUCUUUGAAAUUUAUUAGAUACUGUUAUGUCCCCCAAGGGUACAGGAGGGGCAUCCCUCAGCCUAUGGGAACACCCAAACUAGGAGGGGUUAUUGACAGGAAGGAAUGAAUCCAAGUGAAGGCUUUCUGCUCUUCGUGUUACAAACCAGUUUCAGAGUUAGCUUUCUGGGGAGGUGUGUGUUUGUGAAAGGAAUUCAAGUGUUGCAGGACAGAUGAGCUCAAGGUAAGGUAGCUUUGGCAGCAGGGCUGAUACUAUGAGGCUGAAACAAUCCUUGUGAUGAAGUAGAUCAUGCAGUGACAUACAAAGACCAAGGAUUAUGUAUAUUUUUAUAUCUCUGUGGUUUUGAAACUUUAGUACUUAGAAUUUUGGCCUUCUGCACUACUCUUUUGCUCUUACGAACAUAAUGGACUCUUAAGAAUGGAAAGGGAUGACAUUUACCUAUGUGUGCUGCCUCAUUCCUGGUGAAGCAACUGCUACUUGUUCUCUAUGCCUCUAAAAUGAUGCUGUUUUCUCUGCUAAAGGUAAAAGAAAAGAAAAAAAUAGUUGGAAAAUAAGACAUGCAACUUGAUGUGCUUUUGAGUAAAUUUAUGCAGCAGAAACUAUACAAUGAAGGAAGAAUUCUAUGGAAAUUACAAAUCCAAAACUCUAUGAUGAUGUCUUCCUAGGGAGUAGAGAAAGGCAGUGAAAUGGCAGUUAGACCAACAGAGGCUUGAAGGAUUCAAGUACAAGUAAUAUUUUGUAUAAAACAUAGCAGUUUAGGUCCCCAUAAUCCUCAAAAAUAGUCACAAAUAUAACAAAGUUCAUUGUUUUAGGGUUUUUAAAAAACGUGUUGUACCUAAGGCCAUACUUACUCUUCUAUGCUAUCACUGCAAAGGGGUGAUAUGUAUGUAUUAUAUAAAAAAAAAAACCCUUAAUGCACUGUUAUCUCCUAAAUAUUUAGUAAAUUAAUACUAUUUAAUUUUUUUAAAGAUUUGUCUGUGUAGACACUAAAAGUAUUACACAAAAUCUGGACUGAAGGUGUCCUUUUUAACAACAAUUUAAAGUACUUUUUAUAUAUGUUAUGUAGUAUAUCCUUUCUAAACUGCCUAGUUUGUAUAUUCCUAUAAUUCCUAUUUGUGAAGUGUACCUGUUCUUGUCUCUUUUUUCAGUCAUUUUCUGCACGCAUCCCCCUUUAUAUGGUUAUAGAGAUGACUGUAGCUUUUCGUGCUCCACUGCGAGGUUUGUGCUCAGAGCCGCUGCACCCCAGCGAGGCCUGCUCCAUGGAGUGCAGGACGAGCUACUGCUUUGGAGCGAGGGUUUCCUGCUUUUGAGUUGACCUGACUUCCUUCUUGAAAUGACUGUUAAAACUAAAAUAAAUUACAUUGCAUUUAUUUUAUAUUCUUGGUUGAAAUAAAAUUUAAUUGACUUUG